AGCCUGAGGUGAGUGUUUCUCCUGCGUUGCUCCGAGGGCCCAAUCCUCCUGCCAUCGCCGCCAUCCUGGCUUCGGGGGCGCCGGCCUCCAGGCCCCCGGGAGGAGAACUCCUAGGGCUACUAAAUCCUCGCUGGAGGCGGUGGCUUCUUAUGCGGGAGGACGUGGCGGAGGGCCUGACUUUGGGAGCCGGGGUCAGUCGGCCUCUGAGGGUUGACUGGAUUGGUGAGGCCCGUGUGGCUACUUCUGUGGAAGCAGUGCUGUAGUUACUGGAAGAUAAAAGGGAAAGCAAGCCCUUGGUGGGGGAAAGUGAUCUGUGAAAAUGGUUCGCUAUUCACUUGACCCGGAGAACCCCACGAAAUCAUGCAAAUCAAGAGGUUCCAAUCUUCGUGUUCACUUUAAGAACACUCGUGAAACUGCUCAGGCCAUCAAGGGUAUGCAUAUACGAAAAGCCACGAAGUAUCUGAAAGAUGUCACUUUACAGAAACAGUGUGUACCAUUCCGACGUUACAAUGGUGGAGUUGGCAGGUGUGCGCAGGCCAAGCAAUGGGGCUGGACACAAGGUCGGUGGCCCAAAAAGAGUGCUGAAUUUUUGCUGCACAUGCUUAAAAACGCAGAGAGUAAUGCUGAACUUAAGGGUUUAGAUGUAGAUUCUCUGGUCAUUGAGCAUAUCCAAGUGAACAAAGCACCUAAGAUGCGCCGCCGGACCUACAGAGCUCAUGGUCGGAUUAACCCAUACAUGAGCUCUCCCUGCCACAUUGAGAUGAUCCUUACGGAAAAGGAACAGAUUGUUCCUAAACCAGAAGAGGAGGUUGCCCAGAAGAAAAAGAUAUCCCAGAAGAAACUGAAGAAACAAAAACUUAUGGCACGGGAGUAAAUUCAGCAUUAAAAUAAAUGUAAUUAAAAGGAAAAGAA